AGAGUCGCGGGUGCGCGCGCCGGCGGCGGAUCCGCAGUUAAAAUGGUCCGAGCGGGACCCGGCCUUUCCCCGGCCGCUCCGCUGACUGACUGAGCCGGCUGGCCGGGCCCGGACUGGUCGCCUAGCCGGCAGGCUCGCUCGCUCCCUCCCUCGCGUCCCCAAAGCUCGCGCCCAUCGUUCUCCCGGCUUCCCUGGGCAAAGCAUGUAGCCCCCGUCGGGCACUCCGGCGGCCCGCAGCUGACGCCCACCCCCCACCGUCGCGUGUGUGCCCGUGUGUGCGUGUGUGUGCGCAGGAAGGGCGACCCCUCCGGGGGCCGAGCCAGCGAGCGGCCUGCCCCGCUGCCGGGAGCCCGCCUCUCUGGGUCUCCCUCCCUCCCGUCCCGGUCCCCCUCCUCGGGGCCUUCUAUAUGGGCCACCUUCUCUCGAAGGAGCCGCGUAACCGCCCGAGCCAGAAGAGGCCUCGCUGUUGCAGUUGGUGCCGCCGCCGGCGCCCUCUCCUCAGGCUGCCCCGCCGGACCCCAGCCAAGGUGCCCCCUCAGCCGGCGGCGCCCCGGAGCCGGGACUGCUUCUUCCGCGGGCCCUGCAUGCUCUGCUUCAUCGUGCACAGUCCCGGCGCGCCCGCCCCCGCCGGCCCAGAGGAGGAGCCGCCGCUCUCGCCGCCGCCGCGGGACGGGGCCUACGCUGCCGCCUCCUCCUCUCAGCACCUGGCGCGGCGCUACGCGGCCCUGGCCGCCGAGGACUGCGCCGCUGCUGCCCGCCGCUUCCUGCUAUCCUCGGCCGCCGCCGCCGCCGCCGCUGCCGCCUCGGCUUCGUCGCCCGCCUCCUGCUGCAAAGAGUUGGGGCUGGCUGCGGCCGCCGCCUGGGAGCAGCAGGGCCGAAGUCUCUUCCUGGCCAGCUUGGGGCCGGUGCGCUUCCUGGGGCCGCCCGCCGCCGUGCAGCUCUUCCGGGGGCCGACACCGUCACCGGCCGAGCUCCCUACGCCCCCCGAAAUGGUGUGCAAGCGGAAGGGGGCCGGGGUCCCCGCCUGCACCCCCUGCAAGCAGCCCCGCUGCGGCGGCGGGGGCUGCGGCGGCGGCGGCGGCGGCGGUGGCGGGGGAGGGCCUGCGGGGGGAGGCGCUUCGCCGCCCCGGCCCCCCGACGCCGGCUGCUGCCAGGCCCCGGAGCAGCCCCCGCAGCCGCUCUGCCCUCCGCCCUCUUCUCCCACCUCCGAAGGUGCCCCCACCGAAGCUGGCGGGGACGCUGUCCGAGCCGGGGGCACCGCCCCCUUGUCCGCCCAGCAGCAGCAUGAAUGUGGCGACGCGGACUGUCGGGAGUCCCCCGAAAACCCCUGCGACUGUCACAGGGAGCCGCCCCCCGAAACCCCAGACAUCAACCAGCUGCCGCCGUCCAUCCUGCUCAAGAUAUUUUCCAAUUUGUCACUGGAUGAGCGUUGCCUUUCCGCAUCAUUGGUUUGCAAGUACUGGCGUGACCUUUGUUUAGACUUCCAGUUUUGGAAGCAGCUGGAUCUUAGUAGUCGUCAGCAGGUCACUGAUGAAUUGUUGGAAAAAAUUGCAUCAAGAAGUCAGAAUAUAAUUGAAAUCAACAUUUCUGAUUGUCGCAGUAUGUCUGAUAAUGGCGUAUGUGUUUUAGCAUUUAAAUGUCCUGGACUUCUUAGGUAUACAGCCUACAGGUGUAAACAGCUUUCUGACACCUCUAUUAUUGCGGUUGCCUCUCACUGUCCUUUACUUCAGAAAGUGCAUGUAGGCAACCAGGACAAACUCACUGAUGAAGGACUCAAGCAGCUGGGCUCAAAAUGCAGAGAACUCAAAGAUAUUCAUUUCGGCCAGUGUUACAAGAUCUCAGAUGAAGGCAUGAUCGUCAUAGCUAAGGGCUGUCUGAAAUUACAAAGGAUAUACAUGCAGGAAAACAAAUUAGUGACAGAUCAGUCAGUGAAAGCAUUUGCUGAACACUGUCCUGAGCUUCAAUAUGUAGGCUUCAUGGGUUGUUCAGUCACUUCUAAAGGAGUCAUUCACCUAACCAAGCUAAGAAACCUUUCCAGCUUGGACCUACGUCAUAUCACUGAACUGGAUAAUGAAACCGUGAUGGAAAUUGUCAAGAGGUGCAAAAAUCUUAGCUCUCUCAAUCUCUGUCUGAACUGGAUCAUAAAUGACAGAAAAAGCCCUCUUUUGUUUUUUUAGGUAUAUUGAGGUGAAAGUUGUAGAGUGACAGAUUACUCCACCACCCCUUUCAGUGAGACUGACAGCACCUUGGCUCAUGUAAAACUCAACGUGGCUUUAUAUAAAGAUUUUUCUAACUCCCCUGAUCUUCUCUGGAUGUUUAUUCUGUUUCUUCUUUCAAAUUUCCGUUGAUUCAAUAAAAAACGGUGAUAUUUAGAAAUAAAGUUCAGAGAGGAUUUGAGCAGGUGUUGGUGAUAUAAAAUAUUUGCUGAGUGCCCAUUGUGUUUUAUUUCCAAGAAUUGUUUUGUGAACAUAUGCUAUAUAUUGUAUUUAUAAGUGUUCAAGGUCUGGAUAGAUAAUCUACCAUCUUCCUGUGAAUGUCAUGUCACAGUGGACUUAGAAUUUUAUUUCAUUUCAAUCCCCUAAUAUUACUUAAUUCUCCUAGAGACUGAGGUUUAAAGAUUGCCCAAGGGGAACAAACCUAUCCAUUAAAUCCAGCAGGCAGAGUUGAAUUUGAGUUUGAGAAUAUUUUGUUUUCUUUUAAAGUUAAGUGGUGUGGAGGAGAGAAAUACUUUUCACCUUGGAGUAUUGAGUGUGAAGUUUGAGCAAUUUUCUAUCAUAAAAGCCUGAAAACUUGGAAAUAAAGAGGUGGCAAAAAUAAUGCUGACUGUUGAAGCUGCUUGGGGGUGGUAUUUAUAGCAGCACCGCCUUGCCUCUAUAGAAUGCAGAGCAAUCUGUCUGCAUACUUAUUGGUGCCUAAUAAUGUGCCUGGUUAGGUGAAGCUUUAGUAAAACUGAAUUUUAGCUUAUUUCUGCAAUCCACUGAAUAGUUUUGUGUAUUGUCUAUGACAUUAUUUGUAUUUUUGCAAAAAGAAUAAUGAAAUAUAUUUUACUGAGUUCUGAGAGGAUUAUAGAAACAGAAUGGAGUCUUUCUAAACUAGUGACGUUAGUUUGAGGUAAGCAUAUUUUUGACACUAUUUUUUUGUAUUCACAUAUUCACAAUUAUGUGUAAGACCAUCCCUAGAAAGAUAGUUUGAUAUUGGAGUAACUAUUAUUCCGGGCUUCCAAACUAUCUUUAAAAAAUCAUGAGGCCAGGCAUGGUGGCUCACCUCUUAUCUCAGCACUUUGGGAGGCCAAGGAGGGUGGACUACUUGAGCUCAGGAGUUCAAGACCAGCCUGGGCAACAUGGUGAAACCCCGUCUUUAUAAAAAAAUUUUUAAAAAAUAGCCGGGCAUGAUGGCACGUGCCUGUUGACCCAGCUACUGAGGAGGCUGAGCUGGGAGGAUAGCUCGAGACUGGGAAGAUUGCUUGAGACUGGGAGGCAGAGAUUGCAGUGAGCUGUGAUCGUGCCACUGCUCUCCAGUCUGGGUGACAGAGGAAGACCCUGUCUCAAAAAAAAUAAGAUACGAAACCAUGCCUUUUCUGUUCUUCUAUCCAUUAGACCUUCUUUCUAAAACCAUGAUUGGCCAUGUAGUGCUAGUGAGGUAAUAGUGUGUGUGUGUAUAUAUAUAUAUAUAUAUAUACAUUUUUUUUUCUGGAGCAAGGAUAAUAGCAAUAGCUAAUAAUAGUUACCACUUAAUUAUACUGUGUUCCAGACACUGUUCUGUUUAUACACAUUGUUUUAUUUAAUCUCUACAACAACCCUGAGGAAGGAAUUAUCCCUAUUUUCAAACAAAGGAAUUAAGGCCCAGACACGUUGAAUAGUUCACAACUAGAGGAACCAAGACUGGAACCCAUUUUUGUGGUCUUCAGAGUUCAAGCUCCUACCAUGAAGGGCUCACUGUCUUCCAUGUCCUUAUUCUGCUUCAGACCUAGAGUGACCAUAUAUCCUGAUUUGACCAGGAUAGUUCCAACCCAUGCCUGUUGUUUUGGCAUUCUGUCGGGUUUAGUAUUUGUGCUGCUGCUGUUCCUAAGUUCCAGAAUAUUUAAUUUAAAUGAUAAAUUAAAUGGUCAUCCGACCUCAGACAUCAGACAUGGUUGAUCAUUCUGAACAUGGUUAGAAUGGUACCUUUGCUUUUCCAUAUGGGAUAUCUAAAAGGUGACAUGUUUGAAUAUUUUACUGCAUAUAUCAAGUUGUGGAUAUUUUAAAAAACAGCUUAUUUUUGGUAAAAAGUAAUUUUUCCAAUUAACCCCAUUUGUAAAUACUCUUCAUUUCUUAUGAUGUUUCUUGAGGAAAAGUAGAAAAUUUUGCCCAUUUUUGUGUUUUGUACUACACAUGACUCAUAGUUGGUCUGAAAAAGAAUUUCACUAAUGAAUUUUGAAUAGGUAUUUAUUUAACUUAUAAUGAUGCACAAUUAUUUUUACAAAUGUGUCACUAUCUGUAAAUGCUUCCUUGUAGGUUGUAGCGAAUACUUAACCAUUGCAGAUUAAAGGAGACUACUGGUUCUAAUACUUUGAAUAAGUUGUCUUUCAAUUAAAAAGAAGAAAGUUAUCUUCAUCAAAUGGUUCAGUACCUUUGGCAAGAAAUAAUUGGCAAAAUUAAUCUCUACUUUUUUAAGUAUGUGGGUUUUUUCAAAUAAUUGAUGAUAUUUUGCUACAACAGGCAAAGUUUUUCUGGUAAAAUUAUUUGUGCAUUUAUCCUCAGAUGAAGUUCUUAGUGCAUUCAAAUUUAAAUAAACUUUUUCAGUUGUUUGGUAGGUAGUAGUAUUAAAUAUUAGUUCUGAUAUUGAUUCUUUUAGUACUUAUAGUUAUUUAAUAUCAUUUUUAAGGAAAUACUACUUACUAUGUAACACCAGAGUAUUUAACCUAGUAAAAUCACUUUAAAGGAAAAAUCUAUAUGAUAUGUAUAUAUUUCAGCCUGCUUUGACUUUUAACUUCAAGAGAUGAGAUGGGACUGAAUUUGAUGUGGGUGAUUUUGGCUUAUUGAUUCUCCAUGUUGACAUUAUUUUGUCUAAUAGAAUAAUGUGAAUAUUUAUUAUGGUCCUAACAUGUAAUGGUAAUUUUUAAUUUCUGUGUUGUCUUUGGUUCCUAGUGAGCAAUAGUGCAUAAGUGAACAUUUCUACAAAUACAAAUAGUAGUAAUUAAGAGCUCCCAUAGAAUCAUAUUACGGAUAUUUCUGGAUGUGCUACUCUAAAUGCUGCAACUGCUUUUGUGUUUUUCAGGCCAUAAAAAGAUGAGUAAACAGAGGUACGCAUUUAGCUUGCAGUAUUUAAACAUAUUUCCUUGUUAUGAAAUCAUAAUUUGUUUUUAAAUUAUAGGAAAGAAUGAGAUACAUUUUAUAUGAUGAUGAAUAUGGCGUUAUAAGCCCAUGGAUUUAGGGACAUCCUAGUCUCAGAUCUGUUUUAAAAUUGCCAACAAUGAAGAAAAUCUUCAUUUAUUGAUGAAAAUGAUGAUACCUUAUUGACUGCUUGGACAAAUUUAUACCAUCUCCCACUUCUCCCAGGAGUUGUCUUAUUCUUAAUUCACCAAACCAAAAGUGGCAAUUAAAAUAACUCAUUGUUGUCAAAAUUUAAAAAUGUGUGAUAAAUGAAGCCCAGUAAAUAGUGAAAAUAUGAGAAAGGUGAUUAAAUCUGACAAUUUUCUUGUAAAAGACUUGAGAUGAUAAAUAUCUCCUGUGAUUAGUUAUUAAUUUAGUGCAAGGGAUUUUGCUUCAGCCUAAAAUAUUUUAUGAACAGUGGCAUAUAGAAAUAUUUUAGAAGAUAGGUACACACAUGCUUAACCAUAGGAGAAAUUGCUGGAACUUGAUUGGUAAUAAUUAAAAAUGGCAGACAUGACAUGCAAGUGUCUGGGCUAUUUUCUGUAUGACAGUCCUUUCAGAGAUUAGGAAAGGGAAGUGUUUCCUGAAGACAUGAAGAAUGACAGAAUACUUUCAGCUUGAACCUUUACGCUUCAUGAAAAUGGAAAGGUUUUAUGUAUAUCAUUCUUCAACUGAUAAAACAUUUAAUUUAAGACAGUAUACAAUUACUCCUCACUUACUGAAGUAUGAAAAAUAUCAAAGUUGUUACUUAACAAUUAUAGUUGCACUGCUACUAAUAAUUUCCCUUAAAAUGAAUAUGAAUUCCAUUUAAAGAAAAGAUGAAAUAAUAAUGUUGAUUGUAAUGAAGUGCUGUAUCAUGUUACUGUCUAGCUGAAUCUAUAGCGCAUGGCUCUGCUGGUGGCAUAUAUUAUUGUGCGGAUGUGUGACGUUUUGUUUAUGAGUCUUUCUCCUUGUGAGGAGGACCUGGAUCUUCAUCUUGCGCCCUGUGCCCUCACUUCACAGCCCCCCUCCACCCCUGCUUCCAAUCAGCACCUCACACACGGCCCUGCUCAGAGGAUUAAUUUAAUACAUUCGUGUUGGGAGAAUUAUAGAUCAUGCUUUUGUAUGAUGAAUAAAUUUUCUUUUAAAUUUGGCUGAAACUCUGGCUGAAAUCCAGGCAAUUGGUUCAGAUUCUCCCUUUCUAACAGAUUUAUUUAUUUCUGAAUAAAGUUGGUGCUUCAUAAAGUGAAAAUUUAAUGUCAUUGUUCGGAUUCAGAUAGAGCUUGCGUUAUGUAUUACAUGCCAUUUGUCUGAAAGCCAUAGCCUCAUUUUUGAACAAGGAAUAGAAUUCCAAUGUUCAAUCAGUGCAUUUUGCCCUUUUAAUAGGGACUUUGGAAUACUUUGAGUGAAGAAGUGAGGAACCAGAAACUUUGCCUGCCUUCCAUUUAUACCUGUGUUAAUUGAAAAGAGGCUGAGGAGACAGUUGCAGCUUUUUUUUUUUUUUUUUUUUUGCUUCUUUGUGUAAAAAGUAUAGCUAUAUGAGAAAAAAAAUUGUAUGAGUUUUUCUUUAGCUCUUCUUGUAGUACUUUUAAGUGCUUCUUUUCAAAUGUAUAUUUAGUGUUUGGUUAAUUGCUACUAUGAACCUAAACACACUGAUUAAGGCCAGGUUCACAUUAGAACAAUUAUCUGGUUAAUUGCUCUGGUGCAAAAAGAGGCUAAAAAUCAUCAGAACAUCAAGUUGUGAAAGCACUGGCAGGAGUUUCAAAACCACCAAGCAUACCUACUGCAAAUCACAUCAGCAAAGCAAUUAAUUUAGGCUAAUUGCUUUUCUGUUUGUUCAAGAUGCACUUUGGAACUGUCUUUUGAAAUGGUGGCAAUUAAGAUUAGUGAGCAAUAUAAUUAAAAAAUGUUAGAAUAGUCACUAUUUUUUAAAAGUGUUAACUAUUCCAUAUAAACCUGUACAAUAUAUCUCUCAUCCAUAUAGUACUUUGAAAUAAUUAAACAAAAUAAGGUUAUUUAAUAUAUUUAUAAGAUUUCCAUAAGAAAUAAAUUGAGGAGUAGAUUACCUAUGCCUGAACUAUAGCAUAGGGUUAUCUUUAAUCCUAAUUUUCAGUUAGAAUUAUCUAAUUUCAGCAAUUCAUGCUAUGAUAGCUUGCUGAAUGUGGUGAGAAAUAGCUAGCCUCCAAAGGUGAUAUUGGCUACUGGCAUUUUCUCCAGUUGAAUGUAUGUUUGGCUUCUCAUAUGGCUUCUCAUAACAUAAUCAGGAUUUUAAAAUAAAUUAACAACCAGAUUUGACACAAUUCACAUUAUUGAGGUUUUCCUUGUUAUUAACUAUUAUAAUUUUGGCAGCACCAAUUUGUCAAAAAUUGUAAGCUACUUAAGUUUCCAGCUGUUUCUCUAUGAAGCAGUGUUGUAGCACAUCCUCAGCUGAAAAGAAUGACAAUUUUAGGGAUCAAUUUCUUGUUAGGAAAUGUAGAAAUACCAUUAUUGGAGGAAUACCCUUUCAUUCCCCAAACUGUUUCUCUGUUCACCAUAUUGUCAAACAAGCAAGUAGCUCUUUCCUUUACCUCUGUCUUUCCAUAGAAGCAAUUCUUACGCGGUAUGUUUAGUGACAUAUCCUGCCCCAUUAAAUUGUUCAAAGAAAAUAGGUUGUAUUGUAUUAAAGACUGUGGCUCUGCAAAUGAAUCUUUUAGAGAAACACGUGUUAAAGGAAGUCCUGGUAGCAAUUAUCAUUUCUUUACUGUAAUAAAUUUGAUCUCUUCAUAAUUCAGUAUGAAUAGAUCUUUGGACAUAGCUAAUUAACUACAUCACAAAAUUAAAAUUUUCUCUAGGGAUUAUUUUCUUUUUUUUAUUUUAUUAUUAUUAUACUUUAAGUUCUAGGGUACAUGUGCACAAUGUGCAGGUUAGUUACAUAUGUAUACAUGUGCCAUGCUGGUGUGCUGCACCCAUUAACUCGUCAUUUAGCAUUAGGUAUAUCUCCUAAAGCUAUCCCUCCCCCAUCCCGGGAUUAUUUUCAUAGGAAAAAAGUAUAUGUGCUUUUUAUAAGGAUAUAUUUUUCUUCUUUUAUAAACUUCAUGUUUUCUAGUAGUGCUACAUACUCAAUCUAGAUUUCUUGGUGAUGCUAUUUGUUGUGGAAUGUUCAAUUAGAAAACUGCUGUUGGCCGGGCACAGUGGCUCACACCUGUAAUCCCAGCACUUUGGGAGGCCGAGGCAGGUAGAUCACUUGAGGUCAGGAGUUCGAGAGCAGCCUGACCAACAUGGUGAAACCCCGUCUUUACUAAAAAAAUACAAAAUUAGCCAGGUGUGGUGGCUCACACCUGUAAUCCCAGCUUCUUGGGAGGCUGAGCAGGAGAAUCGCUUGAACCCAGGAGGUGGAGGUUGCAGUGAGCCGAGAUUGCACCAUUGCACUCCAGCCUGGGCAACAAGAGCUAAACUCCAUCUCAAAAAACAAUAAACAAAUAAAAUAAAGCUGCUCUUGUAGGUAAAAAUAUCAAAUUAGAUGGAAAUUUAUUGAUUAGAAAAAAUAGAAAAGUGUUGAAGGCUCUUAAAACACAGAAAAAUCACCCAACCAAGCAACUUAAAUGAUGGUAUCAGACGUUGAGUCUGGAUCUUGGUCUUCUGUUGAAAUCUGUGACUGAAGCAGCAGAGUAAUAUUACUUCAUGUUGGGGAAAAUGCAAGCUAGUACCUACUUUUGUCCUUCAGAACUUCUGUGAUUAUUUGUAGUUGAAAAUAUAGGUACUAUAAAAAUUUCUCUAUUUUGUAGAAGAUAGAAGAUGUCAAAGUAUAGACACAAUUUCUGGCUGUAUUUUUAUAUACGCACUCUUUUGUGCAAUAUGACGUUGCCUGUCCUCCCAUCAAAAGGUGGAGUCUUUUGCUUUAUCCUUCUAUCCUCUUAUAUCUGUGCUGGCUUUGUGACUUGGCUGUGACUGAUAGAAUAUGGUGGAAAUUUCGUUGUGGGCCUUCUGAGCUUUGGCUUCAAGAAGCCUUGCAACUUCUGUUCUUGCGUUUUUGGAAUACUGCCACCAACAUGUGAAUAAGCUCAGACUGGUCUCUCUGAGAAUAAGAAAUCACAUGAAGAUGGAAGUCUAAACAACAGCCAGAACCAACUGUCAAACAUGUGAGUAAGGCCAUCUUAGACCAUCUAUAUUAGUCUGUUUUCACGCUGCUGUUGGGGACAUACCCGAGACUGGGUAAUUUACAAAAGAAAGAGGCUUAAUUGGACUCUCAGUUCCAUGUGGCUGGGGCCCUCAAAAUCAUGGCGGAAGGCAAGGAGGAGCAAGUCACGUCUUACACGGAUGGCAGCAGGCAAAAAGAGAGAGAGAGCUUCUGCGGGGAACUCCUCUUUUUAAAACCAUCAGAUCUUGUGAGACUUACUCACCAUUGCAAGAACAGCAUGGGAAAGACCUGCCCCCAUGAUUCAAUUACCUCCCACCAAGUCCUCCCACAACACUUGGGAAUUCAAGAUGAGAUUUGGGUGAGGACACAGCCAAACCAUAUCACUAUCCAAUCUUAGUCAAGCCUUCAGAUUCCUGCAGUCCUUUGUAGUAAAACUAGCAGAAUUGCUUGGCAAAGCCCAGUUCAAAUAGCCAGUCCACAGAGUUGUGAGCAAGUAAGAGUUGUUUUUUUAAAGCUACUAAAUUUUGGUGUGGUUUGUUUUACAGCAAUAAAUGACUAAGAUACUGACUUUGUAGCUGCCCUAUGUGGGGAAUUUUAUAUUAAGUCAGGCUGAGAGUUUUUCAUUCAUUAAGUUAUUUAAUUAUCACAUUAACUCCAUGACAUAGGUAUCAUUAUGCCCUGUUUUAUAGAUAAAGUAAAAUGGAGCACAGAUAGGUAGAAUGUCUUGCUGAAGAUCACAGAUAGCAAGUGCAGAGCCAGGAUUGAAUGUAGAUCUGUCUGACCUCAAAGCCCCCACAAUAUCCUAGCUGUUAAACUGCCUCCAACACCUUAUUCUGAAUUUAAAAAUAUAGUUGGUUGCAACAAGCAGUUAAACUUACCUUGGAGUCCCUGAAAUACAAGUGCUAGCUAAUAACAUUACAAUAAAGUAAGUAUUAAAUAAAAUAAAUAUUACAAUAAAAUAACAUCCAUUUGCAGUUUCCAGUACUGCUAUUUAAUCUUGAGUAUUCAUUUAGAGAAUGCAUGGAGAAAAAGGCACCUCUUCAGGUCUCAUAAGGGACUGAGUCUGAAAGGGAGAAUGUGAAAACAAAUUUUAAAAUAUAUAAAUAUAAGCCCUUGACUUUAUAUACAUUAAAGAUAGUUUUGGUAUUUCGUGGUAUUAAAUAUCUGUGUUCUUUUCUUCUCUGUUGUUGAAUUAUGGAGAAAUUGAGAGGGGAAAGAAGACCCUUCCUUAGAAUAGUUGUUACUGUGACAUAAUCACCACUAUAUUUAUGCCUUCAACAUCUACGUCUUUUGAUAAAAAGUCUUACAGUGCUGGGCACGGUGGCUCAUACCUGUAAUCCCAACACUUUGGGAGGCCGAGGCGGGCAGAUCACUUGGGGUCGGGAGUUUGAAACCAGCCUGGCCAACAUGGUGAAACCCUGUCUCUACUGAAAAUACAAAAAUUAGCCGGGCCUGGUGGCAGACACUUAUAGUCCCAGCUACUUGGGAAGCUGAGGCAGGAGAAUUGCUUGAACCUGGGAAGCGGAAGUUGCAGUGAUCUGAGAUGGCACCAUUGCACUCCAGCCUGGACGACAGAGUGAGACUCUUGUCUCAAAAAAAGGAAAAAAAUAGUCUUAUAAUAACAUAACUUCUAUGGUAUAUAUGUAAUAAUGGUACUAAUAUCUACCAAAAACUCCACAUAUAGAAAUGGGAAUCUUUAUUUUUGAAAUUCUUCUAACUAAUACCUUAGUGACAGUACAUCCAUAAACUAGUUAAUAUUAGUUGGUGAUUCUGACAUGUAUAUAAUAUCUUAUCAUACCCAUUUACCAUAGUGACACACUAAUCAGACCUGCCUCAGAUUUUCUUGCUUGUUAAAUAUUAAUGUCUGGGAGCAUUUCCUCCAUGAUUUAUUAUGGUAUUUUGAGAGCUAUUUUCAUUUGGGAAAUAUGAUUUCCAUUUGUUUUCCUUUUAACUUGAAUUUAAACUGAAUUCCUAUUUUUGGUGUUGAUAUAAUUUUUUUUCAUUAAUAAAUUACCAAUGAUUUUAAUAUUGUAUUGUGCACACAUGCACAUAAAUAUUUUGCUAUGUGUGAAUAUAUAUUUGGAGAAUCUUAUGUUUGGGGAAAGAAGGGAGAGAGUAAGUUACAUUUUUUUCUUUUAGUUUUAAUUUAUACUCAGAUGGAUUAUAAAUUUUUUAGAAUGUUACAUUGUUAACAGCAUGAGAGUUAAAACUAUAGCCAGGAAUUGUGACUUUUCCACAAUCUUGGGCUUCUAAACAGAAGCUCACUAAAUGCAUGUUGAUGGAUUGAUUGGAUAGCAAUCAAACCUAGUGAAUAUAAGCCUAUGUUCAAGGUAAGAUAAAAGAAAAUUGACCUACUCAAGUUGAACAAGAUAGAAUAAGUCAAAAUAAGUCUGUAAAAAUCUUCAAGUUCAUUUAUUGGGGGUAGACACGGCCCUUAAAAAUACUCUGUAAAUGUAAUGGAAGAGUUAAAGCAGCACUCACUGAAUUCUCUAACAUAGAAUGGUGGCUUAUCUGUGAGGUAUGUGGAUUCAGUUUUAGCCUAACUGACAACGUGUUAACCUUACUAGAUUUAAAAAAACUAAAUACAGGGGGAUAAAAAUGCUGGAGAAACAUAACAUUCUUAUGGCGACAAUUUAUUUGGAAAAGAGAUGACAAAAUAUGUCAAGACAAUGCCCUGGCUUUCUUCAUUAAAGUUAGUAAAUGAAUUUGAAGGAAACCAAAACAACAGUUGUUUUCUAUAACAUUUCUUUCUACAGAUGUAUAGACAUUUAUGGAAUGACUAUCUUUGAGGAAAUAGAUAUUACUUACAUAGAGUUAAUAUUUUGGAUGUUAUGAUCUUGUUGGAAUUAGAAGCUUUCAGUAAUUUACAUCCUUAAAUAGAUUUCUAUCUUCUUUUUAUUUCCAAGAUUUUUCUCACAAGUUUAUUCCCAGUACAGAGACAUCAUUAUGUUAUAGAGGAGCUUUUUUGUGUGAUAGCUCUUGGCAGCCAUCCAUCUGUAAGUAGGACAUAAUAGUGAAGCUUGUUAGAGGGGGAGAAGUGUAAAGUAUUACCAAGCAGGCCCUGACAGGCAUUUAGACAUCCACGCAGACAUUGCUGCUGCUUGAUGGCCGUCUUCCAUUGUGACAAAUGUAGCUGUUUAAAAAGGGACAAGGUCACAAUAACUUUACAAUGCUACACUCCUGUUGUUUAUGGGAUGCACAUAUAUUUUACUCCUGAUUCUUUCCCCAGUGACAGUAUUUUCCUUAUGUUUAAUUUGAAUGGUUUUAUUUUUCUUUACUAACUUGCCACUCUUAGUUGUACACUAUAUUUCAAUCCUCUAAAUGGGUUCUCUAUGUACAUGUUGCAGUUGGUAAAGCAUUUAGAAUUUGUGAUGAUCCACACUGGUUUUCUUGGGGGUAUGCAUGGGAGAGAACAUGGAAUAGUAAUGCAAAGUGGUAGGAAAUCCUAAAUCGCAACUCUCUGUGUUUUAUUAAUGCUUAUAUUAGCAUUGAUUUCACUUCAGCUAGGUGUUGGGAGAAUGAUGUCCUGCAAGCAUUUAGAUAGAGCAAACUGCCUGGGAUUCCACCUAGGUAGAUUAAUCUUCAAAACAGUUAAUCCUUAGGCCAUUAAUGGAAAGUCUACAUAUGGGUUAUUUCAAACGUUCUAUUAAAGCAGUCAUUUGGAAUGGGCCAAUCAUAUAUGUAUGAAAAUUUCAGAGUAUACAAAAAAUAUAUUCCGUUCAUCAGUAAUGAGCUGCAGUCAUUCUUUGGAUAAUCACAUUUGUAAGCUAGACCCAUUUGAAAGAAAGAUCUCUAGUCUUAGUGUAAAAGUAAUUUUCUCCAUGAGAUCACCCUUCCCCUUCCCCUCUCUUUUUUAAAUUUCAAGAGAGUAGGUGUAUUCAACUGGGUUGUUUGACUUUAAGUAUUUAUAUAAGUGAAACUUACUUUCAAAGACUGCAAAGUGGGAAAAUCAACAACUUUUGACUUUCUAUUUUAAGGGCAAUUGGAGUAAAUUUUGUUCAAUUUUUAUUUAAUUUGCUGUGACUACUUUUGACAUUCACAAAUUAUGUCAUUCAUUUUGACACACAAAUAGGAAAGUGAAUAACUUUGGGAUUCAGAUGUGACAAGCUCCUCACAGGUGCCUCCCAUCUCCUCAUUCCUCCUUUCCCCAGGAGCAACGAUAUGAUCUCUAAAAGAGAUGUAGUUUUUCCACCAGCUUUUGUAAAAUGAGUCUUUCCGUUUCUGACCCUUUAAAGAACAUUUGUUUCUUGGAUAAUUUUUUCCCCCUUUAAGUUGUGUCUUCUUCCCUUUCUUAAAGCUGUGAUCUGUCUACUUUUUUUCUGAUGACAUUUUCUCAGGUUAUUUAUUUCCCCUUUAAUAUGGAUCUUCUUCACUUUCUUAAAUCUGUAGAAUAUUUUCUUUUAUUGUUGUCAGUGUCACUGAUGACAUUUUCAUCUGAUUCUUGACAUAUUCAUUUUAUAAAACAUGGCUUUGUAAGGAGUUUUUUGGUCACUGACAUUUUGGCAAACACUUGCCAGUGGCCACCAGAGAAGGUCAGUUAGACUCAGAGCAAUUACAUAAAUUACCCUGAAAGACUUCUUCAAAUACCUGUGAAUAGAGCUUGCAGUGGGAGCUAGGAGACUGAAGUCCUUUAUGUUUUUGUUUUUGUUCCAAAAUUUUAUCACUGGGUCAUUCACUAACCUUGCUAAACUUAUUAAGUUCUCUUUUAUGCUUGUGGUAAUGGGAACCCACCUUAGUGAAAUGUUUGGAGGCUUAAUCAUGUUUCAAAAGCACCUUGAGCAUGAAUCAUUAGUUCAUUAUUAGAAUGGUGGCUUGGGUGGUGCCAUCAAUCAUCGAUGCUUUAUCACCAUCUUAGCCUCAUGGUUUUCUGCAAAUUGACAGUGAAGGUCUUAAAUCAAACUUUGUAAAGACGCUAGCAGAUUCUUGAAGGUUACUUAUUGCUUAUGGUAUGGUAGCACUGAAGUGUGCACAAUUAUCUGAAGAAAAUAGGACAAUUAUAGUGUACUCAUUAUACUAUCUGUUUUCAGAUUAAAUGGACAAAGUGCAUUCAAAUUCAUAAUAGAGAUUUAAAAAAAACACAAUGAUCUCUACUUAUAUUUUAUGCUGCCAUAAAAUAAGAUCUCUUAGUAUAUAGCUAUUUUAUAUUUUUGUGAAAUGCUUUUCACUUGGAUUUUUCAUCCAAACAUAUUUUAAUAGUUACAUUUAAAAAUAUAUAUUUUAACAUUAUCUGCACCUACACAUCUAAUGGAUUAAUAGGAGAUUCAGUGAAAUUCAAAUUAUUCCAGGAAGCAUACCUUUUAAUUUCUAAUUUCUAGCUCAGUUGAGAAAAUGAUCUAGUGACUGAAAAUUAACUAUUUACUUUGAGUGUUUAUAUUUAAUUUUGAACUUGAUGUAUUCCAAGAAUCAAAGGAUCUGAUUGGAAGUAGUGUCAAAGGUCAGCUAAUUUAGCCUUCUGCCAGCAAGCUCUUGACUCUUUAUCUAUUGCGUAUAGCUUGUUGUUUUUUGCUUUUCAUCUUUUUACCAUGUUUUUUUCAUAUAUCAUCUGGGUCCACUUUGUUAACAUAUCAAAUCACACUCUAUCUGAUGUUCAAAAUGCUUCUUACAACUAACAGAUCAGCACUGUCUUAGAGUAUUUUUUAAAUCAGGUUAUUUAUUAUCAGUUUUUUAAAAAGACUAUAACACAUCAUCUUAACUUUGGAGCUUAGAAACGUCUAUGAGAUAUGUUAAAAUACAGAGGUGUCUCCCUGGAGCAUGUGUUUUGCAGGAGUAGAACAAGGAGGGCACUGUGGACUGCCUAAGGGCAAACUGCUAGAGGUAAGACACCGGCAGGUGCUUAUUUUUCUUUGCUUGGGUCUUGCUCUGUUUUUCCAGGCCCAUGCAUGCAGGUAAAAUGCUAAUGCUGUUUAUUCCAUUUUUAUUGGCAGCUCUCCAAAUUUGAUUAUUGAUAUAUCUGAAUUACAGUGGAAUGCAACAUCAAAGUCUCACUUGACUCUUUCCUGAGAUAUUUGUCAGUAGAAUUAUAUAUAUACCUCAAUGUCAGAUAGAUCAUAUGUACUUUUUAAUCUGUAUGAAAGUGAAAUGUUAUAAGGGAACUGUGAACUGCUUGAAAAUGAGUUUUUGGUGGGAUAGUGAGGUGUCUCACGUGGGUUUCUUCCUUAGGUUACUAUAUUAUUUCACUCCCUGAAGAAUAAUCAUAUUUUCAAUAACAAGCACUUAAGUGUGUUUGUGGAUUUUCUUUGUUGUUCCCAUUUUCUGUGCUUUGGUAUUUCAUAUCUUGUACAAACUGACUAAAGUGUACAUUAAUAAGCAGCAGAUUAAUAAACACUGCCACUUGUGACUGGUAGUGGAUGGAGGAGUUUUCAUGUUCCUACAUGCUCUUUUUGAAAAUUUUAACCACAGACACUCAGAAUUGUAAAGAACUCCCGAGCAGGACAACCCAUCUAACACCUAUAUUUUGCUAUUUUGAAACUAAGGCUCAAGGAUAAUCUGUGACCUGUCCAGAUUCAUGCAGCUAGUUAGUGAUGAAGGUGAAGCCUAUAUGCUGCUUUCCAUUAAUUGUGAGGCUUUUAUAUCCCACUAUUCUCAGCUACUCCCUUGCCUUUCUUUAUUAGUAAUUUAUUUGUCACCAACGUUUGUUUUCUUUCAUGGUCUAGAAUUGACUGUAGUCUCUAGAUUGUAGGCCCUUGUAUUUCUUUUAUGGUCCUUUGAAUGGAAAAUAGCAUACACACAGUAGAUUUUUAGUAAAUAUUUUUUAAAAGAAAAGACUACUUAAAAUCCCACUAUUCAGAGAUUUCCACUGUUUACAUUUACAUCUUUUCAGUUAUGUGCAUAUCCAUGUGUAACUUACCCACUUCCUUCUGUAAUUACACUGUCUGUAAUAUUUUGCAAUUGGUGCCUGUCACUCAACUUCUUUUUGUUUUAAUAACUAUAGAACUAUACCACCAUUUCUAACAGGUUAGUGGUAAGAUUUUAGCACAGUGUAUUUAACAAAUCUCUUAUUAAUAGACAUUCUGACUAUUUCCAAUUUUUACUCCUAUAAAUAACUGUAUGAUAAAUAUUCUUAUUUCUAUAUCUUUGUAUACUUUUUGUUGUCUCCUUAGGAAUAAUUUCAUGAAAUCGAAUUUCGAUGUCUGUGUCUCUUUCUCCAUACCUAUGCCAAUUGUGGAUGCUAUCAUCAGCUAUUUUGGAGCAUUUAAAAAUGGCUUUAAGGUUUAAUAACUGACAAAACUUGGAAUAAGUUAUUUAGGCACAAGUGUAUUUUUCACUAAGGGGCAGAAUACUGUAGUAGAUACGAGCAUCAGCUCUGGAGCCAAACCAUCUGGAUUUGAAUCCUGGCUCUGCCACCUUCUACCUGCUUGUCAUUGCGCAAGUUACUUAACUUCCCUGUUUCUCAUCUGUAAAAUGGAGACAGCAGUAGUACUUACUUCAUAAACUUAUUGUGUGAUUUAAAUGUCAUUGUACAUGUGAAGUACUUAGAAUAGUUCCUGGCACAUAGUUAACUACUUAAUACAUAUCAGUUAUAAUAAUGAUAAUUAUUAUUAUUAUCAGUCAGUGAGUAUUUGAUUUCUACCUACAAUGAUGUUGGAAUGUGGAAUUUGAAAGGAAAUUUGAGACAUUACCACCACAGUGUUCAAAAAAAUACCUGCCAUAUACUGGAGGAAAUAAGACGUUAAGUAAAUGAAAGUUGCAUAAUUAGGUUAAAUAAAGCAGAACUACAGCCUAAGAAGAGGCUUGGACUAAGACAUCGUUAAUUACCAAAUGAGUGAUAUAUUCAUGAAAUAGGGUCCUCUUGUAAUACUUGGAAGGGCAAUAAUGAAGUUUGUUCUACUUGUUUUUUAUUCUAACAGGAACAAACCUUCUGAUUUAGAGUGAUCAUGUUUUUCACUUGGUGCACCACAGUCCUGGUUCGUGUAUGGCUUAAUGUCAUGGUUGGAUAAUAAAUUAAUUAUGUGCUUAUCCUAUUUCCUGUUGAUAUUUUCUUUCUUUCAGUGUCCUUGUGAUGUCAAUUCUUGCUUUGGCUUAAGAACUAUUUUGAUUACUAAGGCAUCUUUGCUCAUUUGUUCUGUUUCGGAGUAAUUUUAUAGUUUGAUUUAGAGGACAAUCUUAUUUUCAGGUGCUCAGGGAAAAGCUCAUACUUGCCUAUCUUGUACUGCUUAUAAAUAUCAGGAGAUAAAAUCUGGAAAAAUAGUUUAUUGCCAGGUUUUAGAUGACCUAGCAUGUUGCGUUAAGAUAACCAAUAAAGACUUUAUUUUUCUGAAAUUAAAGAGAGCAGUAUUUCAGGCAAUUAGGUGGAAAGUUUCAAAACUAUAAGUAAAACAAAUCCAGUGUUUCUUAGACCUCUAACAUAUAAUUUUGCACAGAAGUUUGCAUGUAAUGCUAAACAUAUUUUGACGAAUAUGUAGUUCUCCAUAUCUUCAGUACAGAUUUUAAAAAAUGUUUUAAGGCCAGAAGCAGUGGCUUAUGCCUGUAAUCCCAGCACUUUGGGAGGCCUAGAUGGGCGGAUCAUGAGGUCGGGAGAUCGAGACCAUCCUGCCUACCACGGUGAAACCCCGUCUCUACUAAAAACACAAAAAAAUUAGCCAGACGUAGUGGCGGACGCCUGUAGUCCCCGCUACUCGGGAGGCUGAGGCAGGAGAAUGGUGUGAACCCGGGAGGCGGAGCUUGCAGUGAGCCGAGAUCGCGCCACUGCACUCCAGCCUGGGCGACAGACCAAGACUCUGUCUCAAAAAAAAAAAAAAAAAAAGAAAAAAAAAAGUUUUCAUGUCCUGCAUUGUUGACAUCUUAGCCCAUUUUCGUGUAUUUGUCAGUUGAACCUUCUUAUUUCCUUGCCUUUGGUGUCACAAUAAUACAUUUAAAGGAUUGAGAGUUUAGUCUUUGAAUUAUGAAUAAAUGGUAAGGAGAAUAUAAAGGAAUAGAGGUUGACUCUCUGAUGGGCCCUGGCAAAAAUGAAACUUUUUAACCUCUUUCGUUGUAACUGUCUUCUAAUUAGAUAUUAUCAAAUGUUAGAGGAAAAUGCUUGUCACAUUUGAAUUUAUUAUGUAGGAAAUUUAUGCUCUGAAUCAUAAUGGUACUAGAUGACUUUUUUCUGAUGUAGUUAAGAAUAUUGUAAUAUAAGAGUUUGAUCCAGUACAAUUUGUAUUUUUUAAAAUCAUUUUUAAUAUGUUAGGCACUGUGCUUUGUACUGGUGAUACAUAGUUGAAUCAGAAAUGGGCUCUACUCUGAGGGGUUAAUAAGACCUAGGGAUGGCUACUUAGGAUUUCAGAAACCUCUCUGCACAUCAAUACAGAAUAAUACCAAUAACCACUAACACUUCUAUAGCACUGAUUCUGACAGUUACUAUUCCAAAUGUUAUAUAUAUAUUAAAUUUCCGAUAACCCUGUGAGGUGAUACUGUUAUUGUGCCCAGUUUUCAAAUGAGAGAACCAAGGCACUAGAGAUUAAAUAACUUGCCCAGUGUUGUAUAGGUAGAAAACAAUUUUCUAUCCCAAGUGAGCUAUUUUGAGAAACAUUAUUCACAUAUCACUGUUUUGUGCCUUAUAAACAUUAUGAGAAGUAGUUGCUAGUGCAGUUCAAGAAUGAAUAUGUGGAAAUUACUGAAUAUAAUUUCAUUAAUUCAUUUACCAGAUUUUUGUAUGUUUGUUUGUUUGUUUUUUAGAGACAGAGUCUUGCUCUGUCACCCAGGUUGGAGUGCAGUGACAUACGUCACUGUAACCUUGAACUUGUGGGCUCAAGCAAUCCUCCUGCUUCAGUCUCCCGAGUAGCUGGGACUACAGGGGCACACCACCACCACCACGCUUAGCUAAUUUUUACAUUUUUUAUGGAGAUGGAGUCUUACUCAGGCUGGUCUCAAAUACCUGGCCUCAAGCAAUCCUCCUGCCUCUGCUCCCAAAGUGCUAGGAUUACAGGCAUGAGCCACUGCACCCAGCCCCAGGUGUUUAUUGAGCUCCUACCUUGAUCCAGCAUUUGGAAUAAAGCAGUGAGUAGAACAUUUGGAUUUCCUACCUUCACAUAGUUUAAAAUUUAACAUGAAUUUGCCACAGAAUUAAUAAUUUAGCAAUAUUUGCCUCAUAGAGUUUAUAAUUUAGCAAUAAUUGUAUAAUGCUUUUGCCACUUUACGUUUUCAUAAUUUCUAUUUAUCCCUUUUAACGCUGCUGAGCAUGCUCUGAAACCUUAUUUGCUGUUCCUAUAAUUAAUGGUCUCCAAUUUGCAUACGUGGACAGUUUUUAAUUACUGUAUAUUGUACUUUUCUUUAACCUAGAUUUUCACACAUUGUACAAUAAAUUCCUUAACCUGCCUUUUAUAUGUCUAAGAUCAUUGCUCUUGCUGAUGAAAGAUGGUCCCUGGUUCUCACUUAGGUUUUCUAACUUACUUUUAGGAACUACUAACAGGGAUAUAGUAUUUAACUAAAAAUUCCUAUUGCAACCAAAUUUCUUUACAUAUGUGGAGAAAAUGAAUAUGCUUUUAUUAUCCUAAUGAGAAAGUAAUCCUGGACCCCGAGUUGAUUCAUUAUUGCCCAGUGGUGUGAAUGCCUGCUGGUUAUUACAGCUGAUGAGGAAGGUCUAACCUCUGUGUAGAUCUUGGGAUGCAAAUGGGUAGCAAUUUGUGAAAAGAAUCAACUUACUGGUUGAGUUUGUGUGGGUUUUUUUGUUUGUUUGUUUGAGACAGAGUCUUCCGCUGUCGCCCAGGCUGGAGUGCAGUGGCACGAUCUCAGCUCGCUGCAACCUCCGCCUCCCGGGUUCAAGCAAUUCUCCUGCCUCAGCCUCCCGAGUAGCUGGGACUACAGGCACACACUGCUACGCUUGGCUAAUUUUUUUUUGUAUUUUAGUAGAGACGGGGUUUCACUGUGUUGCCGAGGCUGGUGUCGAACUCCUGAGCUCAGGCAGUCCGCCCACCUGGGCCUCCCAAAGUGCUGGGAUUACAGGUGUGAGCCACUGCGCUGGGCUGGGGUAUGUAUGUAUGUAUGUAUGUAUGUAUGUAUGUAUCUAUUUGUUGAUUAAUUAUUCCCAACAUGCCACAGUUUUUUCUCCCGGGACUCUCUUAACAGGCUACCAUUUAUGCAUAAUCUUGGAUGUUGAAAAAUAAAUUCUCUUCCCCUACCUCUCCUCCAGGAACCUAGUGUUUCCCAAUGUGGAGGCUUAAAGGCUUGGGAACUAGUUGACCUUCUCAGAGGCCCAAAAGCAGGGUGAAGAAAAGCGUUCUUGUUCUCAGCAAGGGAAAUGGCUCCCUUCACAGCCUCAGCCAUAAAUCCUCUGGGUUGACGGCAGCUAACUUUCCAAUAAGGCCCUUGUCAAGACUCUUACCUCCCCACAGAAUUAUGUGGGCCCAAAAAAGGUGCAUGUGCAUGGACCACAGUUUGGUGUUUUAAAUCAUUAUUAUUUUUAGAUCUUUGAGAGUAAACUUCUCUCUUCUCUAGUCCUUUCUCUAACUGUCUUAAAUAAUAGCUGAAUUCACUUUUUGACUUUAAACCCUGUUUUUAGGUCUAGUUUUAGUCUUCAGGGUGGCUGCCUCUAGUAUAUGAAAAGGGCUUCCCUAUGGAAUUUUUGUCUGUAGUUCAGAUAUUCAACUAAACAUAGGACAUAAUUUAUGAAAAACUAUUCUUCUUAUUGGUUGCUCAUUUUGCCCCAGUAGAAUGCCAACCCAGUUCACUCUAUAUUCUCAAAGCUACUAACUGAGAACUUUCUUCUUCUUCUCUUUGUUUCACAAGAAAGUAGUGGUUUGUCUAAUUACUAUACUGUAGUUACAAUUAUAGAGAAAAGGUCAGUCUAGUCAUUGCCAAUUAAAGUAGGAAAAAGCUACAUUUAUAACCACUAAGAGCCAUUAUAUCAAUUUAAUGCUGUUCAUCAGUGUGUAACCCGUUUUCUAAGACAUAUAAAUCUAAUCGUGGUAUUAUAGUACACUUACCCUAUUAAAAGCCUUUGGUGCUGCAGAGAAGAGAUUAUUGCAAGCAACCUAUAUUAACUGUAUGUCUUUUCAUUGUGGCUCAUCAUAAAUUUUAAGAUCUGGGUUUUGUAAAACCUGGCCAACGUGAGUACAAAUAGGUCCUCCAAAUCACUGGUUAGCCCUUUUAUUUUUAGGUAUUUGACAAAGCAAAAUAAUCUGUUGAGAUUAAGGUUUUUCUAAUUUUUUUUGACAGGGAUAUCUAUGUAAUCAUGCAUUGUAUACUAUUGCAAUCAUAUUUCUUUUUACAUAUAGAGAAAGUGUAUAAAUUUUUACUCUCCUAAUGAGAAAAUAAUCCUGGGACCUAAGUUGAUUUAUCAUUACUAUUUCUGCUUUUAUAUCUUCAUGUAGUAUUUAGGGGAUUUUGGCUCGUAAAAGACAUCGUGGAUUUAGUACAAGUUAAGAAAAUAUGAUAGAAAUGAGAUAUUUUCAUUAAUUUCACCCAUUAUUUAAAGUCUAUCCGAACACUUUUGAGUGUAUCUUUACACGAUGUUUUAGUCUAUUCAGGUUGCUAUAACAGAAUGCCAUAAACUGUCUUAUAAAUGACAAAAAUUUAUGUCUUACAUUUCUGGAGGCUUGGAAGUUAAGAACAGAGUGCCAGCAUUGUUGGGGUCUGGUGAGGGCCCACUUCCUCGUUCAUGGAUGGCACCUUCUCACUGAGUCCUCACAUAGUAGAGGAAGGAACUACCUCUUUGGGGUCUCUUUGAUACGGUAGUGAAUUCCAUUCAGAAGGACGCUGCCUCUGACCAAUCACUUCCCAAAGGCCCCAUCUCCCAAUACCAUCACCUUGGUGGUUAGUGUUUCAAAAUAUGAGUUUUCAGGGGACACAGACAUUCACACCGUAGUAUAUGCUAUGCAGGUUGUAUCACACUAUCAACGGAUUAUUACAGAUCUGAAAGGUUGUCUUCCUAAAUUGUCCUUUGCUGUAGGAUUUUUAUGGAUCAAAUUUCAUCGUGUUUUGAAGUAAGAAAAAGCGAAAGGAAAGUCGUUUGGCUUAGAUUUUUGAGGGAUAUGAGAAAAUACCUACAUCUUGAUAUUGAGUUGUAGAUUUCUCUGUUUAGAGUAACUGUCUGUAGUAAUAAGGUCAAGGACAUUCUGAUCUUUAUUCUCUGAUACCCAUCUAAAUCUAAAAGAUUGCAUUACUAAUUGAAAUACCACCACUCACUUGUCAGAAACAUUUAUAUUAUGCUGGUUCCCUUUUCCUUGUUCCAGUGAGAUUCCAGGUGUAUCUUCCACUUUUUGAAGCUCUCCAUAGCUAUAUUUAUCUCUUCUGGUAUCUUCUACACCACAGAGAAAAUGUAAAACCAAAAAGACUCAUCAAGCUUUCUUUUAUUGUUUUAGCUUCCAGAUGCUAUUGUCUUAAAUUCCCUAAUCUGAAUAUUUCAUGGUUGAUUACCUUAAACUUCCUACUGAGCCUAGUUUGCUGUAAUUAAAACCGGAGUUAAGACAUUCCACUUAUCUGCAUAAUCAGUGACUAUUAUCCUGAUUCUCUAGAAAUCAAAUUUUGGAUGAAUUGAUUUUAGGAUCUUUAAUCCUUGGUCUGUAUGUCACCAGAAUAGUGCCUGGCCCUGUUCCUUCUGCUCCAGUCUCUCUAUUUUUUUAAUGUUUAAAUAAUGUCAGCCUCUACCUCCCCUCACCCUGGGCACAUGGAUGCACAUGUGCAAAUGUGGAUGCACACACACACACACACACACACAGACACACACACACACGCCCCACUGUCACUGCUUUACAGUUAUAGUUUUAUUUGUGGAAAUUUGAUAUCUUUAAAGUAUUUUAAGACACACUACUUCCUAGUUGCUUAAGCCCCUUUUUUGAGGUUUUAAUUUUCUUAUUAAAAUUUCUGUAUACUUAAUGUUAAAUUUACUUUUAUGUAUCCAAUAAGUUUUUGGCUAUUGUGAAUUAUAUUGGUUCAGUGUUUUCUAAUUCGUUGUUGGUAAAUGAGAAUAUACUUUUUGUACACUUUAAUAUACUUAUGGAUACUAAUUUUAUAAUUGAUCAUCUUUCUGAACUUAAUAAUUUUAAUAGUUUUAUAGAUGAGUUUUAAUAGUUUUAUAGAUGAGUCUCUUGAAUUUGAAAGUAGACAGUUACAUCAUCUGAAAAUAAGGAUAAAUUUGCCCAGUCUUCUCUAGGAUUUUUACCUUUUAUUUCCUUUAUAUACCUGAUUGUAUGUUCUAGAUAUUCAAGAGGCAAGUUUUGUAAGUAAAGUUUGAUUAUUUACAUCUACUUCUUGCUUUUUCUGUGAACUUUCCCUCUUUUCUUUUUCUUCUCUAUUUUUUAAGCAGACACAUUAAAUGAAAUAAAAUGGCAAUGAGUAUUAAUGGAAAGUUACCAUUGUCUGGGAAGUUAGGGUUGAAAGGUGGUAUAUAGAUAGAAUUGAUGCAUUCAUUCUGCUUAACAUUGAACUUUUAAAAAGCUAAACUGGGUUACAUUUUUGUUUUUAAUUUCUAUCAAGUAAAAAUUAGUGGUUCUCAGUUUUUUUUAAUAUUUUCUUUUUCUCAAGUAUUUAUAUUUCUUAAAAUAUGGCUCAGCUCAAACAGUACCAUUAUAUGAAUUUAUUUUGCAUAUAAUAUGCUAAAUAAUAAUUUACCUACAGAUUUUAGUUUUAGUUUUUUUUUUUUAAAGAAAAAUCAAAGUUCAUUUCACUGGUUAUUGAGCCUUCACAGACUGUUUCUAAAACUGUUCGUAGAAUACAGCAAACAUGAUCUUUUGAAAUAAAAAAGUUUUAUUUGUGAGUUUUCCUAUAUUUUCCCUUUAAAAAAACGAACCUUCCUGUAAGAGAUACCUUGACAUGUUUUCAUGACUAGAUCUAUAUGAAAUAAUGUAAUUUAGUAGUGAUUUAGAAUUUUAGGACAUUUGUUCACGGAAUGUGUAUUAAUACUACUGUGUUGUCAAAGGAAAUGAAUUAUUUGCAAUGGAAAAGUCUUUUGGACAGAAACCUUUCCCCUUUCAUUUAUUUAUUUAAUUUUUUUCUCUAAUUAUAUCACAUUUGUAUGUUUUCCCUAGCCUAGUUUUUUUUUUUUUCCAGUUUGUUCAGUGCCAUAGAUAGGAGUGCAUGAACUGGAAAAUCGAAUACUAGAUGAUGCAUAUUAUCAGAUGGUAGGUAUUUGCAUAUCUAAGAGCUAGAUCUAACUCUUGUGUUUUGUUUCAUUGUAUAAAAUAGAUUUAUUGAAAUUCUUAUUUUUAAAUAUGGAAAAUAUAGAUUAUUUAAAGAAUGAUUAGAAAUAAAGUUAUAUAACUUAAUUUUGAAAGACUGUUAGUUUAGUCCUUCAUAUAACUAAUUGUCUUGGCCCUCACUAAUUUAAUUGUUUUAAUUUUUCUGGUGUCUGUUUGCCAUGCAAAUGUGCUAACAUAUUUGCAUUAGAAACAAAUUAUUAUUCUUGGAACUUCAGAUUAGAGCACGAGUUUAAUUGCUCCUUUUAAUUUUUUCUUUUGUUUUUAUUUGAUAUAUAAAACUAAAAAUAUAUUUCAAGGAAAAGCAAUUUUAGAUAGAGUCACAAAGUGAUUCCUGAAACUUGCUUUUAUGAAAUAAGAUGAAAACUUAUUUAUACCAAAUAUUUUUAUAACAACACAUUUAUAAUUUCUUUAAGUAAGGAAAAAGCAAAAACAAUUAGGGAUUGAUUCCUAAUAGGAUGCUAAAAUUUCCACAAACUUUGAUACUUUCUUUACUCCAGGAAAUUUUAACUCUCAACGUUGUAAAAAUGAUGACUUAAAAAAAAUACUUCGGUUUAAUAUGUCUAAGAUAUAUAAAUAGGAUUAUGUAGUUACAACCCAUAUUACUGUACAUGUUUCCAGAAAUUAUUUAGUGAUAUCAAAUAUAUUGAUUUUUUUCCUAUGUUGAGUAUAUACAAUUUACAUUUCAUAGAGGAUUUUGUCUUCUCAAUUAAUUUUAUGAACUCAAGUAUAUAUAUAUAUGUAUACUGAACACCUAAUAUAUUCUGACACUGUGCUAGGUGCUGGACACAAAAAAGUAAAUAAAUAACGUGAUCUCUUAUCAUAUGUAUGAACCAAUAACUAAAGUAUGAUCUGAUGCCUAUUGUAAUAGAAAUCAUGAGAAGGAAAAUUAAAAAUAAGAAUAAUUCCCUAUUAGGGUUAUAGCAAAUAUUCUUCCCAAGUUUUAAUAGUUUAUGGUGGAUAAGACUGUCCUCAGCUAAUCUGAACUGUUUCUAGGUUGCUUCUUUGAAAUUAAAAUUAAAGCUACAUUUUAGUGUCUUUUUUUCCAGCAAAAGGUAGCCUUUUUAUUUAUAGUACUCUAAUUUUCCAGGCAGCAUAUAAGAAUUAUGUAAUUUUGAUAUGCUAUAAAUUAAAUUUUAAAAGCAAAAUGCAGAGAAGGAUAAUAAUUAAAAUUGAAAAUAACCUGAGGGCAUAAAGUGUUUAUUGCAAGAUGGAUUCCUUAAGGAAUUCUUAUUUUUAUUUUUUGUUCUAAAUCAUAAUUUAUUCUAGGACUAAUUUAUAUCUGAACUCUGAUGGCAUUUUAGGCGUUUACAGAAAAUCAGUUUAUGGACUAGGAGCUAGAGAAAUUAGGAAGGCACACUUGUAAGUUCAUCAGAAAUCAAAAUAAAUUCUUACUAAGCAUUCCAGGGAUCUGCUAGUCAAAAUGUUGCUCAUUGUUCAAAGUUCAGAGAGUUUUACCCCUCCUAGCUACUUGGGGGUUAAUUGUAGAGCCCACAACUAAAAUUUUUCUUUUUUUUUGAGACGGAGUCUUGCUCUGUCACCCAGGCUGGAGUGCAGUGGUGCGAUCUCGUCUCACUACAACCUCCACCUCCUGGGUUCCAGUGAUUCUCCUGCCUCAGCCUCCUGAGUAGCUGGGAUUACAGGCACGUGCCACCACGCCCGGCUAAUUUUUGUAUUUUUAGUAGAGAUGGAGUUUCACCAUGUUGCUCAGGCUGGUCUUAAACUCCAGACCUCGUGAUCUGCCCACCUCAACCUCCCAAAGUACUGGGAUUACAGACGUGAGGCACCGCGCCCAGCCUAAAAUUUGUAUUAAUCUCUCAUCGGAAACCACAAACAGCUGUAAGAACCUGCUGUAUGUAUUAUAAUAUCUCAGUUUUUUCUGUCCAAGAAACUUCACCAGAGGUUUAAAAUGUGUAUAUAUAUUGUAUUUGAGUUUAUAUGUGUUUAAUUUGUUCCCUACUUGGUUACAAAAGAUUUGAUCAGCUUAUCAUGAAUAUUAGUUUUAUUAGAUUAAUUUUACUGGUAGUUAGAGGAAAGUGGCAAAUUAGGUUAUUUUUUCUUAUUAAGUCUGAAGGGUGGCCUGAUUUCUUGUUAAUCUCUAAUCUGUUCAUUCAAUUUAUGGAAAUCCCGUUUCUUGACUUCAUUUUUUGCUUCCUGCUUUCAGAGCAGUCUGUAAGGAUUAGGUCCUUCCUAAUUUCUUUGGUGUUCAUUGGUCUGUUCAGGGGUAAUGGUUGGCUGGGUCUCCUUCAUGGUUCCUCUUUUCACCCUUUUCAUUCAUCUUUUUAAAAAUAUUUUUUGUCCUCUUUUUUCAUAUAUAUACACAUAUAUAUGUAUAUACAUAUAUAUGUGUAUAUAUAUACACAUAUAUAUGUAUAUACAUAUAUGUGUGUGUGUGUGUGUGUGUGUGUGUGUGUGUAUAUAUAUAUUUUUUUUUUUUUUUUUGAAACUGAGUUUCAUUCUUGUUGCCCAGGCUGGAGUGCAAUGGCGCGAUCUUGGCUCACCGCAACCUCCGCCUCCCAGGUUCCAGCAAUUCUCCUGCCUCAGACUCCCGAGUAGCUGGGAUUACAGGCAUACACCACCACGCCCAGCUAAUUUUGUGUUUUUAGUAGAGACGGGGUUUCUCCAUGUUGAGGCUGGUCUCGAACUCCUGACCUCAGGUGAUCCGCCUGCCUCGGCCUCUCAAAGUGCUGGGAUUACAGGCGUGAGCCACCAUGCCUGGCAUAUCUUUUUUUUUUUUUUUUUUUUCAGCUGUGAUCCUUUCCACACUGUUUUCUUUUUUUCCUCCUCUGAAUUUACGUGUCUCUGUUUUCUGUAAUAUCCCUUUCUCUCCUCUCUCUCUCUCUCAUUCUCCCAUUUUGAAGAUAAUCUUGUUCUUCACUAUCCAAAUUCAAUGUUUGCUGUUUGAUGGAAGGUGGAACACAGUUGAGUAAAGUAACCCACCAUUUACCUGAUGUCCCAGUUAGCAGAUUUGAGGAGUGGGCUCAUUUGGGCUAUUUGUUGGCAGAUUUGAGGCAGAUUUGUUGGCAGAGUGAGCUCAUUUGGGCUAUGUGACAGUUCCUAUAUAGCCACAAGAAAGAAACACUUCCUGCAAGAAGGAAAAUUGUACAGGUUAAUUGGGCCCUGGACACCUAGUUGGUUCAUAGAUACAGGUAUAAACGGUGUUUGAGCAUUUUGGAUGUUUUAAAAACAGUUUUUAAACACAGUUUUGCACAAUAAUUAAUCAUCUGUAACCAGUCCUGACAACAGUGUAGAGAGUGUUCUCAUGGAUUGAACCCUGUGUCAGAGGAUGGUUCUGACUUUAAAUGAAGCUCCAUGUUCAAGAAGGCAAGCUGGCCCAACCUUGAUAUUUUUUUUAAUGAAAUUUCCUAACUCUUAGUCACAGAUGUUAUUGUCCAUGGACCAAGUGCUGAUCAUGGAACUGUGGGGUUACCACCUAGUAGAUCAGCAACGUGAAGGCUGGUCUCUACAAUAAAACUUUAUCUUAAAUUCUUAUUUUCUCAUUACUUAUACCUUGUAAUUCUUUUUCACAAAUAUUUAAUAUCAGGUUUAUUGAGCCUACCAACCCUGCAAAGUAUGCAGAACAAAUUGUAUCAUUAUAUUAAGUGGAAAAACUAAAUUCAAAGAAGUAGCUUAUCCAGUGUUAUCCUGCUAGUUGGUUAAUUCACUUCAGUGCCAUGUAUCAUAAUGCUUCCUAGUUGAAUAGUAGUUUCCAAAUAAUAAAAUAGAAAUUUUUAGUUUAGAUCCAUAUUUCAAGAUUCAAUUUAUAUGCUACCGUAUCAGGAUUGCCAGAUAAAAUAUAGGCUGCUGUAUUAGUGUGUUCUCACACUGCUAAUAAAGACAUACCCAAGACUGGGUAAUUUAUGAAGAAAGAGGCUUAACUGACUCACAGUUCCACAUGGCUGGGGAGGCCUCACAAUCAUGGUGAAAGGCAAAGGAGGAGCAAAGUCACACCUUACAUGGCAGCAGGAAAGAGAGAGAGAGCAUGUGCAGGGUAACUCCCCCUUAUAAAACCAUCACAUCUCAUGAGACUUACUCACUGUCAUGAGAACAGCAUGGGAAAGACUUGCCCUCAUGAUUCAGUUACCUCCCACCAGGUUCCUCCCACGACACAUGGGAAUUAUGGGAGCUACAAUUCUAGAUUUGGGUGGUGACACAGCCAAACCAUAUAAGAUGCCCAGUUAAAUCUGAAUUUUACAUAAACAAGAAAUACUUUUUAGUAUAUCUCAUGCAAUGUUUGCAUUUUUAUUUACUAAAUAUGGUAAUCCUGUAUCACUUCCAGGGGUCCUUUUCUAAUUUUCAUGCCUCUCAACAGAAGGAUACAUGAUGCUCCCUGAAUUCCAGGAUAUUUUUUUCUCUCUAUGGUACUUUGUAUUUCACUUUACUUUUUGUAAAACUGACUCUUCAUUUUUAUGAGACUGAAAGAUCCUGUAGUAGAGGCAUUUAGUUUUAAGUAUCUUCAUGCUGUAUCAGCUGACAGACUGAAUCCUUAAAUCCAGUAUCCUGCUGAAUCAUACUAGAGCCCGAGGCAAAAAUAUAGAAGAAAGUAUGCCUGUAUAUGCACUUAUCAGUAUAUCCCCUCAUAUUUUGUACCAAAUGAAAAAAGUUAAUAAAAGCUCUACAAUAAAAAAAAUUGACUAUAUAGAAAGAUCCACAAUGCCCGACCUGUUGGACACCAUUGUGUCCUUCCAAGUGGGGGACUCCACCAGUUAAGUAGAAAUGACCAUUCUCAUUGCAUAAUAGUGGAGGAUUAUCAAACAACAGCAGCGUUAAUUUAAAAUGUUGAUAUUUUGUCCAUCAUAUUGCAUUAAUGUUUAUCUUAAAAAAUAUUGUACUAAAUUAUUAUCUUGACUUUUCAGUGUUUUGGUACCCCCUUAAAUUUUGUGCUUCUGGUUAAAUCUUUUGAGAGAGUGCAUGGAGUUGUUUCAUUUUAGUAUCUACUUAAUGUUUUUAUGUCUAAGUCACCUAUGUAUUCAGGUUCACCAGCGAUUCAAAAUCUUGAGGACCCAUUGAGUUCUUUCUUUUAUAAAUGAAGAAACUGACCACAAUGGGAAGGUUGAGACCACAAUUUCUUACUUGCUGUGAUUUCUGCUGACCAUUUAGGCUUUCCUGUGGAAGAAGGAAUCAUUUAACUCAAGCAUUCUUGUUGCCUUUGAUAUCAAAGUUCUUAAGAAUAAAGAAUGUCAUUGGAGCA